GAGCCGAGCCGAGCCGAGCCGAGGCGAGCAUCUCCCACCGCCGCCGCCCCGCGCCCCAGGCGCCCGCCCCCCACCCGCUCCAGCGCCCUGCCGCGGGCCAAACCUCCCCACCAUGCCCCGCACCCCGCCCGCUCCUGCGACCCCCCAGCCCCGCUCAGUCCCGAGCGCCCGCAGUCGUCGCGCCGCCGCGCCAAGCAUGCAGUAAAGGCUGAAAAUCUGGGUCACAGCUGAGGAAGACCUCAGACAUGGAGUCCAGGAUGUGGCCUGCGCUGCUGCUGUCCCACCUCCUCCCUCUCUGGCCACUGCUGUUGCUGCCCCUCCCACCGCCUGCUCAGGGCUCUUCAUCCUCCCCUCGAACCCCACCAGCCCCAGCCCGCCCCCCGUGUGCCAGGGGAGGCCCCUCGGCCCCACGUCAUGUGUGCGUGUGGGAGCGAGCACCUCCACCAAGCCGAUCUCCUCGGGUCCCAAGAUCACGUCGGCAAGUCCUGCCUGGCACUGCACCCCCAGCCACCCCAUCAGGCUUUGAGGAGGGGCCGCCCUCAUCCCAAUACCCCUGGGCUAUCGUGUGGGGUCCCACCGUGUCUCGAGAGGAUGGAGGGGACCCCAACUCUGCCAAUCCCGGAUUUCUGGACUAUGGUUUUGCAGCCCCUCAUGGGCUCGCAACCCCACACCCCAACUCAGACUCCAUGCGAGGUGAUGGAGAUGGGCUUAUCCUUGGAGAGGCACCUGCCACCCUGCGGCCAUUCCUGUUCGGGGGCCGUGGGGAAGGUGUGGACCCCCAGCUCUAUGUCACAAUUACCAUCUCCAUCAUCAUUGUUCUCGUGGCCACUGGCAUCAUCUUCAAGUUCUGCUGGGACCGCAGCCAGAAGCGACGCAGACCCUCAGGGCAGCAAGGUGCCCUGAGGCAGGAGGAGAGCCAGCAGCCACUGACAGACCUGUCCCCGGCUGGAGUCACUGUGCUGGGGGCCUUCGGGGACUCACCUACCCCCACCCCUGACCAUGAGGAGCCCCGAGGGGGACCCCGGCCUGGGAUGCCCCACCCCAAGGGGGCUCCAGCCUUCCAGUUGAACCGGUGAGGGCAGGGGCAAUGGGAUGGGAGGGCAAAGAGGGAAGGCAACUUAGGUCUUCAGAGCUGGGGUGGGGGUGCCCUCUGGAUGGGUAGUGAGGAGGCAGGCGUGGCCUCCCACAGCCCCUGGCCCUCCCAAGGGGGCUGGACCAGCUCCUCUCUGGGAGGCACCCUUCCUUCUCCCAGUCUCUCAGGAUCUGUGUCCUAUUCUCUGCUGCCCAUAACUCCAACUCUGCCCUCUUUGGUUUUUUCUCAUGCCACCUUGUCUAAGACAACUCUGCCCUCUUAACCUUGAUUCCCCCUCUUUGUCUUGAACUUCCCCUUCUAUUCUGGCCUACCCCUUGGUUCCUGACUGUGCCCUUUCCCUCUUCCUCUCAGGAUUCCCCUGGUGAAUCUGUGAUGCCCCCAAUGUUGGGGUGCAGCCAAGCAGGAGGCCAAGGGGCCGGCACAGCCCCCAUCCCACUGAGGGUGGGGCAGCUGUGGGGAGCUGGGGCCACAGGGGCUCCUGGCUCCUGCCCCUUGCACACCACCCGGAACACUCCCCAGCCCCACGGGCAAUCCUAUCUGCUCGCCCUCCUGCAGGUGGGGGCCUCACAUAUCUGUGACUUCGGGUCCCUGUCCCCACCCUUGUGCACUCACAUGAAAGCCUUGCACACUCACCUCCACCUUCACAGGCCAUUUGCACACGCUCCUGCACCCUCUCCCCGUCCAUACCGCUCCGCUCAGCUGACUCUCAUGUUCUCUCGUCUCACAUUUGCACUCUCUCCUUCCCACAUUCUGUGCUCAGCUCACUCAGUGGUCAGCGUUUCCUGCACACUUUACCUCUCAUGUGCGUUUCCCGGCCUGAUGUUGUGGUGGUGUGCGGCGUGCUCACUCUCUCCCUCAUGAACACCCACCCACCUCGUUUCCGCAGCCCCUGCGUGCUGCUCCAGAGGUGGGUGGGAGGUGAGCUGGGGGCUCCUUGGGCCCUCAUCGGUCAUGGUCUCGUCCCAUUCCACACCAUUUGUUUCUCUGUCUCCCCAUCCUACUCCAAGGAUGCCGGCAUCACCCUGAGGGCUCCCCCUUGGGAAUGGGGUAGUGAGGCCCCAGACUUCACCCCCAGCCCACUGCUAAAAUCUGUUUUCUGACAGAUGGGUUUUGGGGAGUCGCCUGCUGCACUACAUGAGAAAGGGACUCCCAUUUGCCCUUCCCUUUCUCCUACAGUCCCUUUUGUCUUGUCUGUCCUGGCUGUCUGUGUGUGUGCCAUUCUCUGGACUUCAGAGCCCCCUGAGCCAGUCCUCCCUUCCCAGCCUCCCUUUGGGCCUCCCUAACUCCACCUAGGCUGCCAGGGACCGGAGUCAGCUGGUUCAAGGCCAUCGGGAGCUCUGCCUCCAAGUCUACCCUUCCCUUCCCGGACUCCCUCCUGUCCCCUCCUUUCCUCCCUCCUUCCUUCCACUCUCCUUCCUUUUGCUUCCCUGCCCUUUCCCCCUCCUCAGGUUCUUCCCUCCUUCUCACUGGUUUUUCCACCUUCCUCCUUCCCUUCUUCCCUGGCUCCUAGGCUGUGAUAUAUAUUUUUGUAUUAUCUCUUUCUUCUUCUUGUGGUGAUCAUCUUGAAUUACUGUGGGAUGUAAGUUUCAAAAUUUUCAAAUAAAGCCUUUGCAAGAUA